GCUUCACAGGCUCCAGCCGAGCGGACAGGCGUGGCGGCCGGAGCCCCAGCAUCCCUGCUUGAGGUCCAGGAGCGGAGCCCGCGGCCACCGCCGCCUGAUCAGCGCGACCCCGGCCCGCGCCCGCCCCGCCCGGCAAGAUGCUGCCCGUGUACCAGGAGGUGAAGCCCAACCCGCUGCAGGACGCGAACCUCUGCUCACGCGUGUUCUUCUGGUGGCUCAAUCCCUUGUUUAAAAUUGGCCAUAAACGGAGAUUAGAGGAAGAUGAUAUGUAUUCAGUGCUGCCAGAAGACCGCUCACAGCACCUUGGAGAGGAGUUGCAAGGGUUCUGGGAUAAAGAAGUUUUAAGAGCUGAGAAUGACGCACAGAAGCCUUCUUUAACAAGAGCAAUCAUAAAGUGUUACUGGAAAUCUUAUUUAGUUUUGGGAAUUUUUACGUUAAUUGAGGAAAGUGCCAAAGUAAUCCAGCCCAUAUUUUUGGGAAAAAUUAUUAAUUAUUUUGAAAAUUAUGAUCCCAUGGAUUCUGUGGCUUUGAACACAGCGUACGCCUAUGCCACGGUGCUGACUUUUUGCACGCUCAUUUUGGCUAUACUGCAUCACUUAUAUUUUUAUCACGUUCAGUGUGCUGGGAUGAGGUUACGAGUAGCCAUGUGCCAUAUGAUUUAUCGGAAGGCACUUCGUCUUAGUAACAUGGCCAUGGGGAAGACAACCACAGGCCAGAUAGUCAAUCUGCUGUCCAAUGAUGUGAACAAGUUUGAUCAGGUGACAGUGUUCUUACACUUCCUGUGGGCAGGACCACUGCAGGCGAUUGCAGUGACUGCCCUACUCUGGAUGGAGAUAGGAAUAUCGUGCCUUGCUGGGAUGGCAGUUCUAAUCAUUCUCCUGCCCUUGCAAAGCUGUUUUGGGAAGUUGUUCUCAUCACUGAGGAGUAAAACUGCAACUUUCACGGAUGCCAGGAUCAGGACCAUGAAUGAAGUUAUAACUGGUAUAAGGAUAAUAAAAAUGUACGCCUGGGAAAAGUCAUUUUCAAAUCUUAUUACCAAUUUGAGAAAGAAGGAGAUUUCCAAGAUUCUGAGAAGUUCCUGCCUCAGAGGGAUGAAUUUGGCUUCAUUUUUCAGUGCAAGCAAAAUCAUCGUGUUUGUGACCUUCACCACCUACGUGCUCCUCGGCAGUGUGAUCACAGCCAGCCGCGUGUUCGUGGCAGUGACGCUGUAUGGGGCUGUGCGGCUGACGGUUACCCUCUUCUUCCCCUCAGCCAUUGAGAGGGUGUCAGAGGCAAUCGUCAGCAUCCGAAGAAUCCAGACCUUUUUGCUACUUGAUGAGAUAUCACAGCGCAACCGUCAGCUGCCGUCAGAUGGUAAAAAGAUGGUGCAUGUGCAGGAUUUUACUGCUUUUUGGGAUAAGGCAUCAGAGACCCCAACUCUACAAGGCCUUUCCUUUACUGUCAGACCUGGCGAAUUGUUAGCUGUGGUCGGCCCCGUGGGAGCAGGGAAGUCAUCACUGUUAAGUGCCGUGCUCGGGGAAUUGGCCCCAAGUCACGGGCUGGUCAGCGUGCAUGGAAGAAUUGCCUAUGUGUCUCAGCAGCCCUGGGUGUUCUCGGGAACUCUGAGGAGUAAUAUUUUAUUUGGGAAGAAAUACGAAAAGGAACGAUAUGAAAAAGUCAUAAAGGCUUGUGCUCUGAAAAAGGAUUUACAGCUGUUGGAGGAUGGUGAUCUGACUGUGAUAGGAGAUCGGGGAACCACGCUGAGUGGAGGGCAGAAAGCACGGGUAAACCUUGCAAGAGCAGUGUAUCAAGAUGCUGACAUCUAUCUCCUGGACGAUCCUCUCAGUGCAGUAGAUGCGGAAGUUAGCAGACACUUGUUCGAACUGUGUAUUUGUCAAAUUUUGCAUGAGAAGAUCACAAUUUUAGUGACUCAUCAGUUGCAGUACCUCAAAGCUGCAAGUCAGAUUCUGAUAUUGAAAGAUGGUAAAAUGGUGCAGAAGGGGACUUACACUGAGUUCCUAAAAUCUGGUAUAGAUUUUGGCUCCCUUUUAAAGAAGGAUAAUGAGGAAAGUGAACAACCUCCAGUUCCAGGAACUCCCACACUAAGGAAUCGUACCUUCUCAGAGUCUUCGGUUUGGUCUCAACAAUCUUCUAGACCCUCCUUGAAAGAUGGUGCUCUGGAGAGCCAAGAUACAGAGAAUGUCCCAGUUACACUAUCAGAGGAGAACCGUUCUGAAGGAAAAGUUGGUUUUCAGGCCUAUAAGAAUUACUUCAGAGCUGGUGCUCACUGGAUUGUCUUCAUUUUCCUUAUUCUCCUAAACACUGCAGCUCAGGUUGCCUAUGUGCUUCAAGAUUGGUGGCUUUCAUACUGGGCAAACAAACAAAGUAUGCUAAAUGUCACUGUAAAUGGAGGAGGAAAUGUAACCGAGAAGCUAGAUCUUAACUGGUACUUAGGAAUUUAUUCAGGUUUAACUGUAGCUACCGUUCUUUUUGGCAUAGCAAGAUCUCUAUUGGUAUUCUACGUCCUUGUUAACUCUUCACAAACUUUGCACAACAAAAUGUUUGAGUCAAUUCUGAAAGCUCCGGUAUUAUUCUUUGAUAGAAAUCCAAUAGUAGAGACAGGGUUUUACCUCCUAUUGGUACUGAGAUAGCAGUUUUCCCAAGAAGCCAAGUACUGACGAGCAAUGUGGAGCUGGGUCUGAGGGGCAACCAUGCUCUGUCUGCUGUUGGGAGCGGGCUGGGCCCCCAGCAAGAAUGGACACACAUUCAUCCAAGGUGACCACCAGUGGACAAAUGGUGACUGUUUGUGUGUGUGUGUGUGUGUGUGUGUGUGUGUGUGUGUGUGUGGUAGAGUCUCACUCUGUCGCCCAGGCUGGAGUGCAGUGGCGUGAUCUCAGCUCACAGCAACCUCCGGCUCCCAGGUUCAAGUGAUUCUCCUGCCUCAGCCUCCCGAGUAGCUGGGAUUACAGUGUCCACCAUCACACCUGGCUAAUUUUUGUAUUUUUAGUAGAGAUGGGGUUUCAUGAUGUUGGUCAAGCUGAUCUCGAACUCUUGACCUCAGGUGAUCCACCCAUCUUGGCCUCCUAAAGUGCUGGGAUUACAGGCGUGAGCUACCGCGCCCUGCCAAGAGCCGGUUUUCCUUUCUCGUCUUUUUAUCCUCCUCUCACCCAUUGCUAGUUUUUAUUCUUUCCUCUUUUGAUGUAGGUUGGUGAUGGGAUCACGUGUGUCUGUUAAGAAGCCUUACAUUUUCAGCUGCCCUCGGACACCUCCUUCAUAUUUUGAUUAUGACCUGAGUUGAAUAGGGCAUUUGCAGAUAUUUUCUGGUACUGUUCGCUGCAUCUACCUCUUCCUAGUCAGUUUUUGUGUGUGUCUUAGCCCUGUUUCCGUUCUGUUCCAAUCAUAAUAAAUGGGUAACACAAAUCCUAGGUCAAGAGUAAGUCUUCAGAAAUUAAGAGAUGAUUUUUAUUUUAAAUGUAAAUCCUGUUUUCCUGGCAUGGGCAGAAUUAAUUUUGCUUUUGAUAUCCAGCACAAGAGGGCAGCAUGAUCUGCAGUAUUUCAGUGAUAUAAUGUAAGAGCACCUCAUUGCAAAACCUGGUUUUUAAUUUAAAGCUUUCUUGGAAAUUCUAUUUUUAUAGCUUGGGUCUUUGUAUCUUGAUAUGUGUUAAUAUGAAAUUUAAAAAGUAAUAUUGUGGCGUAUUAUGUUUGAAACAUGAAAGUCUUUGUGGAAGAUAUUUUUCUGAUGUUGUCCUGGAAUACCUAGCAUUUCAAACAGGGUUUUUUUGGAUUUCCUAAUUACACCUUCUUGACUAGUAACUGGAAUAGGCAGACGCUGACAUCUUGAGUGGUUGGAUGCAUUUUAAUUCCUGAAGCAUACAUUAUGAUUUGCUUGUAUGAUGUUUCUGUUUUCUUUGUAAGCAUGAGUUUGCAGAGAAAGAUAGUUACACAGUUAGUUUCUUUAGUUUUCUUCCACGCCAACAGAGUUAGCAGAGACAUUUUAUUCUUAUCAGGUCUCUACAAUUUCACUCUUUGUUUUGGAGAAAAGAUGAGCGGUUUGUUGUCCUGUUUUCUCAUGCCUAAUUAUGGUGACAUAACAUUUAGCUAAGUACACUGACUCUAAUGGGUGCCAGAUAAAUGUUUACUUGCUUUCAAUUUGUUAAUUUGGCUUUAAGAACCCAAGAGCUGGUGUUGGUAGAAGUGUUUGUUUACUCUCUCAGGGAAGUAAAAGUUAAUAUUGGGUUACAGCCAGUGUGUUUUACACAACUGGUUUUUCUCCAGUGUGUGCGUGGGGAGUAUGUGUGUGUAUGUAUAUUUAUGUUCAUCGAUGCCUUCAACAGUGUAACAAAAAAACCAGAUUCAUAUCAUUCUUUUUUCUUUAUAGAUUAAGGUAAAUGAGAGCUAAAACACUAGAUAAAAGAAAAAAGAAACAUAUUGACUUCUUCCCAUGUUUCUUUUUUUUAAUCCAGUGGAAGAUGCUUGUGGUCACUGAGGUAUGGAAUGCGAAUGCUAGUACUAGAUUUUAAGAUAGACAUAUUCUCCUAUGUUCCCUAAUCAAAAAUCGAGGGUUGCCCCAGUGAUUAAGAUUCUCAGCUUUUAGCCAGGCGUGGUUGUAGUCCCAGCAGCUCGGGAGGCUGAGUCAGGAGGAUUACUUGAGUCUGGGAGGUCAAGACUGCAGUGAGCUGUGAUUGCAUCACUGCACUCCAACCUGUCUCCAAAAAAAAAAAAAGAAUGAUUCCUUCCCAGCUUGACUGAAUGGGAAGUUAGGAUGUGCAUCCUACAGGAAUUGAGGGGAGGAGGGUGGUAGUGGUUUGAACUAUUGUUCUGUUUCUGAAACCUGGAAAGGGACUCUGGAAUCCACUACAAGUUGCUAAAUAAUUUGUGGAGAACUGAAAGCAACCUCCAUGAUGAGCUUUUUAUAUGAUCAGAAAGACUGUCUUGCGAUACUCUAUAAAAUCUGAUGUCCAUAUCCCACUUCCUUGCCAGAAAAAAAGAGUCAUCAAUAAAGAAGAAACAUAAUUGUAGGGAUACCUAUUUAUCUGUUUAUUCAGUUCAAAUGACCACUGGAGUUGGUGCUAAAUGUGCAUUUUUAACAAGUAUAAUAUUUCAGCACUGUCAAAAUUACCUCUACAAUAAUAGGCUUGUUAAAUUAUAGCUCUAUAAGCUAGGGGGUAAGAUGGCUCUGCCCAGCACACAUUAAUCUAUGCCUGUUCACACAAGUGAUUCUGCUGAGCAGGUAGCAUGUUUAAACAAGAAAUACUGGUCCUAAAACCUCUGAUUUAUGGUAGGUGUUGUUUUGACACAGCACCAUUCAGACAAUUUACAAGGCAAAGCUUCGUGCUAAAAUAUUUCCUCAGUGUCAUCAUUCGUCACCAGUAUAAAUAUUCAGUAGUGAUGCUGGAAAAUUGGUAAUAUGCCCAUUGAUGCCAAAUCACUCGCUAUGUUUCCUUUCAAGUGAGAUCUGUUGUGGAUAUGGUUAAAAGAAACUAUGAUUUUUCUUCCUUGAGAGCAGAUGAGCUGUAAGAAAUUGAGAAUAACAACCGUCCUGACAGCUUUCAUGUACUCAAUCUUGCCUAUAUUGCUUUUAAUUCUGGCUUAAGUCCUGCGGGCUUUCCCUCCCACCCCCUUGCCUGAUGCGUAUUGUAAAGAACACAUUUAUAUGUACAUUAGUUAGUUUAAGAGGCUUUUUGUGUUCAAAGGAAGAAGUUAGUCAUCACCAGAAAAGCUUUGUUGCAAAACAAAAACACACAUUUCCCCUUUCAUUUUUUCUUGUUAAUAAUAACAAAUGCAAGUGACUAUAAAGGGAAUAACACAAAAGAUUGCAUCAAUCAUAAUGAUUCUCAAUAGCCACAUAAAUAUUGUUUUUUCAGCUUUGAAUGAAACAGCUAAGAGUUUGAAGUAGGUGUGGUAAUUAAAUCCUGUCGGGUUAUCACAAAUUAAAAAUAAUGUUUUUUUCACAUAACAAUGGUUAUAUGUACUUAAACUCUUAUCAGGGGUGAUACGAAGUCAUAUUUUAUGGGAGUUGCUCCUUUACUGCUAAUAGUAUCAUAAAAGCCUUUGUUAGGAGUUUAAAUAGUUACGUAGUUACAUAUAUUUGAUUGCUAUUGUUAUUUUGUCAGUAAUCUGUAUGUAAGCGAUUACUGUAGCACUUGUCUACAGCUGGUAAAUAUUGCAUCAUUUUGGCAUAAUUUUUAAUCUACUAGAAUGUUCUGAUUCAUGGUUUUUCUCCAUAAUAAAUCAUACAUGGAGAUACUGACAACUUAGUAACAGAGAAAGCACUGUGUUUGUCCAAUAAAAUGUUAAAAAGAUAAAAAACUAGGGAAGAAUGUGCUUUGUUCAAAGUGAUAAUCAUGUAAUAUUUCAGGAAAUUAUAAGAUGACAUUUUACUUAACUGUGUUAAAUUGUUUUCCUAUAGUGUAUAUAAUGUGAUACCUGCAUGUAUUUGUAUAUGCCUGUAUCUCUCUCUCUCUGUCUCUCUCGAUAUAUGUAAGUUCUCCACUUCAGUCUAAUGUCCGUGGCUAUGGUUUUAACGCCCCCCCAUUAACUGAUUUGAUAUGUGUUGUCUUUAUCUUUAUCUUCGGCUAACUUGGAACUAGCUAACUUGGAACUCAGGGCUUUGUAGCAUAUCCCAAUAUCUGCUGUUAAUGUGUGCUUAGUAAUUUGGCAUUAGCCUAUGGGAUGUGUGACUGAUAAUAGUAAUUCAAGUAUUGUCAUUUAAAACUGUCCCCCACUGUUAGAUCAACAUUAUAGUUCUCUGUGACCUUAUUGUCAGAAAAGAAUCAAAGUAUCUUCAUGACUUAGUUCUUAGCUGUUGGAUAACCAUUUCAAGGGAAAAUAGAACACUGUUUCUGGAAUAACCUAAUGAUAUUCCAUUAGCCACUUGCAGUGGCCGAUUUCAACAUGAAUAAAUAUUGAUAAGUAUAUUACUGAGAGCCUAAUAUGUAUAAAGCAUAGUUUUUGGACACUAAGUGGAAGUUGUUGGGAUUUGCUAGCUUGAAACGCUGUUCUGUUUUACUGUAAGGCCAACUGCUUCCCCUCAAAGAUUUGACUUUGAAGUUCUCAUAUGAGAACUCUGGUUUUCAUUUAUAAUUGGAGUUUUAAUUUGAGAGUUUUCCAUUUAUAACUGGAGUUUAAUUUGAGUUUUAUAUGAGAACUGAUUUUCACUUAUAAUUGGAGUUUUCUUAUUCCAUUAUUUUAUUCCUUCCCCCUUUAUUAUAAACAUGAUUAUUUAUAUUGCCAUGAAGACAGUGGAAAAAAAAUCAGAAUAUUUACAACGCUGAGGUUGUGACAUUUUGUUUUCCAUGAAGUUUAAAACAUUUUUGCUUUUAUCAAGUUUUUGAUAGUGUUUAUGAAAAUGAUAGUUACAUUCUAAUUUAGGUAAUUACGUAUUUACCACCCUUGUCUUAUGUUAGCCUUGUUUCCCCCUUGUCUUCCUUGCCUUGUUUUCCCCUUGUCUUCUUGGAGCUUAUCUGUUGUUUCCUUGCUAAAUCCCCUGAGCCCAGGAUUGGAUACACUGUAUCUGAUUAGUAAAUAUUUGUUGGCUGGACAGAACAAGAAAUAGUUCCAAGAGUGCAUUUGCAUCUCUUUAAGCAACACCCAUAAAGAACAAUGGGACUUUACAGUGUUGAAAUAAAAUUAGAGUGUUUUUUGUCUUACAGCUGGUACUUAUAUUAAAUUUAACUCUUGCUUCCAAUUUUCUUUUUCAAAAGUACAGUUUGUAAUAGAUUACUUUGGUGGACUUUGUUUCUGAUACGUGAUGGCCUGAAGAGAAAAACCGUACAUUGGUUCUUUGGAAGCUGUGAUUCAUGGAACUAGACCAAGUUCUCCUGUUGUUUACCAGUCAAAGAAAUGAAACUGUCAAACACCUAAUAACUUUUUUGGGGGUUUAGUUGUGUGUUGAAGGUGACUUUUAACACUCUGUGGGUUAAGCGUCUGGUACUGUAUAGUUUUGUUUCAUAAACUUCAUGCCCUUAAGAAGUAAAGAGAGGAAUUAAUCCAUUUAAAAUCAUCAGUAGACAUUGAAAAUCUGUUCUUGCACAGGGAGUUGAGGUGUUGAGAUGCCCCAAUUCUGCUAGGAUCAUAGUUUGUGGUAACUAAGUCGGUCACAUUACUUCUCUUAGCCUCAGGGUUCUAACAGGUAAAAAGUGGCUUUUUCAUUCAUCAAGCAUUUCUUGGUCUUCUACUCAUCGUCAGUUGUGGUCCCAAACAUUGAAACAAAAGUACCUGUUUUCAAGGGACUUGCAAACUUAAAUAGUUGCCGACAGUGGAUGAUGAUGAUGAUGAUUUCUUCUCCUUCUUCUCCUUCUCCUCCUUCUUCUCCUUCUUCUCCUUCUCCUUCUCCUCCUCCUUCUUCUCCUUCUCCUCCUCCUUCUUCUCCUUCUCCUCCUCCUCCUCCUUCCUUCUUCAUUCUUCUUCCUUCUUCCUUCUUUCCUCUUUGUUCUUCUUCUUCUUUUUUUUUUUUUUUCUUGAGACAGAGUCUUGGUCUGUUGCCUAGGCUGGAGUGCAGUGGUGUGAUCUCAGCUCAUUGCAACCUCCGCCCUCUGGGCUCAAGCAAUUCUCUUGCCUCAGCCUACCGAGUAGCUGGGACUACAGGCAUAUGCCACCACACUUGGCUGAUUUUGUAUUUUUAGUAGAGACAGAGUUUCACCAUGUUGGCCAGACUGGUAUUGAACUCCUGACCUCAAGUGAUCUGCCUUCAGCCUCCCAAAGUGCUGGGACAGGUGUGAGCCACCACACUAGACCAACAAUGGAUUACUUCUAAAAACCAUCCUGUGUCAGAAUCUAUGAUCUCAUAUCAAAAAGAUGCAUAUUAAAAUUAAUGCAGCUGCCAAAUGGAAGUCUAGAUACUUUUCUAGAUACAACACACAUGAGCAUAGCUCCAUCAGAUAUGUCUUCUUCAUAAUUCAUUGGCCUUGAUUUUAUAAAAUUUCCAAAAAUGGUUCUUUUGGCACUUCAAAACCAAUUGUGUUCAAAAGAAAUCAUACCAGUGGGAGUAGCAGAGGUGUUCAGGAAACAAAAUAAAUGAUUCUUUAUUUCAGAUCAUAAUCUCUAAGCUUCAAGUGGACUCACAACAAUUUCUAGCUAGACUCUUGACUGGGCCUAGAUGCUUUUCUGAGCCACUGGGGGAGGUCUAAGUGCUACAGCUCAGCUUAGGAAAGUGUGUUGGAGAAAGGGGAGGGACUUCCAGUGUUGCCCUUUACAAGUACCUGUACACGCUUUGGGCUUUUAGAAGUAUUGAUAGGAGAAAGAACAUAAGUAAUGAUAUUUUCCCUGUAAGUAAUGUUAUCAUGAAAUUCAACUAUGAUUCACUGAGUGUUCUCAUUCUUGGUCACCAGGAUUAAUGUUUGAGAAAUUUCUUCCUCGUUUAAAUAGAAGCUCUUUCAUAUCUCAAAUAAAGACUCGACAAGCUUCAAAGUACAUUUUGAGGCCCUGGCAGUGGGGAAGGGGGAGGGAGGGGGAGGAAAAAAACAGGACAUUUUUGAGAGGAAGUUUAUUAAAAACAAGUUCUCUGUUCUGGAAACAUUUUCCUUUCAUGUCUUGUUUGCAUUUGCAUUUUAAUAGAUUAUAUCACAUAGGCAAAUGUUCCAGCACCUCUUGAACACCUGGAAAGCCUGUCUUAGACUUGUUCUGGUGUUUAGAAAUCUUUAGGCAGACAGUGUUCCAAAUACAGUCAUGCUCGCCAGGCAUGGUGGCUCAUGUCAUAUAAUCCCAGCUACUUGGGAGGCUCAGGCAGGAGGAUCGCUUGAGGCCAGGAGUUUGAAAGCAGCUCGGACAAUAGCAAGACCCCAUCUCUAAAAAAAAUUAGCUGUGCACAGUGGUGUGUGCCUAUAGUACCGGCUCCUCGUGAGACUGAGGUGGGAGGAUUGCUUGAGCCCAAAUGUUAGAAGCUGCAGUGAGCUAUGAUUACUGUAUUGCCCCCCCAAGCCUAGGAAUCAGAAUGAGACCCUGUCUCUAAAACUGUGCAGCAACAUCUGAGAAAACAGUAUAUCUCCCCUGGUUGAUCUUCAGCCUGAUAGUAGCUAAUCAGACUUCUCUCUGAACUUCAGGUGGAAGUUUAUAGAAAUGUUCUUUUGCUUCAGUGACUGGUCUCAUUCCUCACUCUGAUUGAAGCACAUAAUAGAAGAGUUCAGAGAUUUUGGGAGUUGGAGGAAAAAAUAGCAUACCCAGUUCUUUCUGUGUUCCGCACAAUGAUAUUGGAACAGGGAAUAUAGUUGAAGCAGAUUUACCCUUAAAUAUAUUUUCUCCACAUACAAUUCCACACGCCUUGAUCAGCAGCAGUGCUUUGAGGCAUAGUUACAAUCAUGGAUUAUUUUUUUUCAUUACCUUUACAUAUUUAAAAGUAGAGAAGGAAGGAAAUGGUUGCUUUUUUAAAAGUAGUCAUUAUUUUUAAUUUUUUUUUCCUCCUGUUGGUGUCAGAAUGGCCUGGGCGCAUAAAAUUUAUUUCCUUUGGGGGAACUAUAAAUGUAUUCUUCUUCUCUUUUUGGAGAAUAAAAUGGUAGUGACAUCUUACAAUUAUCCCAUGCGAAUAUAAAUCUUCUCUAUAUACUCCCUAUUACUUAGCAUGAAAAUGAAAAGGGAGUCAAGUAUAGUUUAAUAAGUUCUACCAAUGAACUGUAUUGUAGACAGAAGUAUUUCUUAUUGGUGCCAAGUUGGAAAAGUUAGUCUUGACGUGGUCCUGUAAAUGAAAGGAAAAUCAACACAUACAUUUCAGGAUCAUGAGUGAUCAGUGUCACUAGAAAAGUGUUCUUCUUUCACUUUAAGAUUAAAUAAAUAGUUGUUGACAUAAAUAGCCGGGGUAAUAAAAGGGAACACCUGUGUAAUCCAGCCAUCAGCAGUUUUAUCGUACAAUCAGAUAAGCUGCUGUUUGUUAAGGAAUUGUCAAGUCUUUAGACCAGAUGAAUAGAUUUAGCUCAUACGUUAGAGAAUUUUAAAAACUGAACAGAAGAAGCUUUAAUUUCCCUUGAUGCCAAAUGUUCUAACCACUCUCAUCUCCUUUCACACACGAGAAGCUGUAGGAGUUUAAAGCUCAAUUGACCUAGCCUUCAGGUAUGUCUUCUUCCAUUAGUUAUUGCUGUACCAAAGUAGCUAAAUGUUCUAGAUGAGAUUAGGGUUUGAAAUUUUAUAUGGCAAAAUAAGUACCUCAUCAUUUUUGGAUAAACAUGGGGUAUUUUUUUUCUAAUACAGCUCAUCUUUUCUCUCCCUUUAAUUCUCAUGUCCACUUUCAUUUGAUGUCAAAUGAGAGAGAACUUUGGUUGUCAUUUAAGAGCCUCUUGAUCAAAACAGUUAUCUUAAGAAGCAUUGAUUGUGUGUGUGUGUGUGUGUGUGUGUGUGUGUGUGUGUGUGUGUGUGUUGUGAUGGGUAGGGGAGAGGGAGAGAGAGACUUUUUAGUUAGCUUGUCCCACCACAAUAAGAAUUAUAUUUUUGGAUUCUCUUAAUAAUAUGUGAAAUUUAAAAUUUGAAAAUUAAUCAGCAAAUAAGAUGUCCUUUGACUUCACCCACCAGCAAAUGGAAGGAUUUUUCUUUAUUUUCUAAUAGGGGAUUUAAAUCACUAUAUGAUUUGGGAUCCAUGGUACCCUUUUGGUAAAAAGCAUGACUUUAGAAUCAGCCUGCCCAAAUGUGAAUCUCAGCUCUUCCUUGCUGAAUUACUUAAACUCUUUCUGCUUCAACUUAUUUGUAGUAUGGCGAUGAUAUUAACAGUACAAUCCUUUUUUUGUGUGAGUGACAAUUAAGAGAAUCAAUAUAUGAAAAGCAUUUGAUAUGGUACCUAACAGCUAAAAAUUGAUUUUUUUGACUAAUUGAGAUGAUGAAAUUUUAGUAGUCUUAAAAAAUGUACAAAUUCCAAAUUUGCUAGUUUUGAUGAAACAAUAGGAGUCUGGGAAGGGUGUCUGUGUUUUCCUGGAUGCAAAGAAAAAUAGAUAAAUGACCAAGACUAACAAGCCACAAAAGAAAAUCAAUAGAGUAUUUUUUUUGUUUGUUUGCAUGUUUUCUUUUUGGUUGUGUUUUCAAUGGGGCUUAGCUUCAUUCCAGAGUUAAUUUUAAAUUUAAUUUGGUUUUACAAUGAGAGCUCAAUUUUGCAUGUAAGUACCAAACAUCUGGUUUACUUUUUGUUUGAAAACGAUACAGCUGAAGUUGAGUACAGAAGUCUAUUGUGUAAUUAAGGAAAGAGAGUUUGAAAUUUUGUAAAAUAAGUUCUAUUUAAAUGGAAUAUUGGAAUUAUUCCAGAGAAGUGGAUAUACUUCUUAGGAGUAGGAGAAACUUACAUUAUUUUUAAAAAAUGCUAUAACUAGUCCAAAUGUAUAAAUUCUAUGUAUUCACCUUUUUCAAAAAGCAUGAAAAAUGACAAAUUUCACAAGUGAAAGUUAAAGUUGACCUAAGGCAGUUUUAGAUUGUUGAGCCUUCAAAUUUUAUUCAUGGGAUGUUUUUAGAGACAGUCUGUGGUUUGAUCACUCCAGUUAAUUCUGGGCAAUCUUUCUACAUUUCUAUCAGAUGGACAUUCUGAUAUUUUAAAACUUCCUCUUGCGCAAAAUAUGUUUAAAGCAACCUGGGAAGAAAAUGAGAUUUCUGGUUAGUUCUUGUAAACUAUAAAUUAUGUUUUUAAGACAUUUAAAGGAAUUAUAAGCCAAACAUAGAUAACUCCUGUUACUGCACUAUUACCAUUAAUAAACUAACAAUUAAAAUGCCGUAAAGUACUGACUGGAUAUAAUACUAGCAUUGUGAUAUAUAAAAAAUAGAAUUUGGGGUGGAGAGACCUAAAUGAAGAUAGGACACCUACUAAUUUUCCACCUGCUUGCCAGAUAGUUGUGUCUUCAGGCAGAGACACCCAACUAGUCCAGAGUCUUAGGAUUCAACCUCAGUAAUGUCAGAAAGGCCCUCAGCUCUGAACUGCGAUGAUUCUCUCAUUCUGUGCAACUCUUUUAGAAAUAAUUUGAUAAGAGCUUAAGAAAGUCAAAAAUAGGUUGUUUGUAAGACAUCAGAGGAUUUUUAUAAUAGUUUUGCCCCACCCUUGAAUGUUUUAGAGGUCUGUUGUAGGACAGAGGUUUUGGUUUCUGGCAGUUGCAUUCUAGUUCUCUACCAAAUUGAGGAUCAGCCAGAGGUACAAUACAUUUGGAAUCUUGCCCUGUGUCUUAUAAUUUUAUAGCAACAUUAUAAAUUUAUUUGACAACUUAAGCUUAUAAAACUUCUGUCACUUCCGUUGUCUUGUUUCAUCUGCAGUAGCAACAAAGCAACAAGAAAUCUGUUGCAGUCUCUCUGCCUCUGAGCAUCCACACAGUAGAUCCACCCUCUUCUUUGCCUUCUUGCCCAAUACUCUUGUUAUUGUCCCUAUCGGUUUUUAUGUGGCAACCGCAGGGAUGUGAUGCCUGUAAUUGAAAAUUAAAUGAUUGCCAUAAAUCAUUAAUCAGACUGCAGAUUAUAACAGCAUUUAUUAAGCAUCUUGGUAGGCCAGGAGUGUGCUGGGAAUUUUGCAUAAGGUAACCGGUUACUGUCUUGUGAAUUCUGUCUGGGUAUUUUCCUGUGUUUGUUUCUUCCAACUUUUAUUUUUGGUUCAGACGGUACAUAUGCAGGUUUGUUACAUGAGUAGAUUACAUGUGGUGGAGGGUUUGGUAUACAGAUUAUUUUGUCACCCAGGUAAUGAGCAAAGUACCUGAUAGGUAAUUUUUUGAUCCUUGCCCUCCUCCUACCAUAAAGUAGGUCCCAGAAUCUGUUGUUGUUCCCUUCUUUUUUUUUUUUUUUUUGAGAGA